GUCGGGAGCAGGAUGGCGGCGGAGCAGGACCCCGAGGCGCGCGCGGCGGCGCGGCCGCUGCUCACUGACCUCUACCAGGCCACCAUGGCGUUGGGCUAUUGGCGCGCGGGCCGGGCGCGGGACGCCGCCGAGUUCGAGCUCUUCUUCCGCCGCUGCCCGUUCGGCGGCGCCUUCGCCUUGGCCGCCGGCUUGCGCGACUGUGUGCGCUUCCUGCGCGCCUUCCGCCUGCGGGACGCCGACGUGCAGUUCCUGGCCUCGGUGCUGCCCCCAGACACGGAUCCUGCGUUCUUCGAGCACCUUCGGGCCCUCGACUGCUCCGAGGUGACGGUGCGAGCCCUGCCCGAGGGCUCCCUCGCCUUCCCCGGAGUGCCGCUCCUGCAGGUGUCCGGGCCGCUCCUGGUGGUGCAGCUGCUGGAGACACCGCUGCUCUGCCUGGUCAGCUACGCCAGCCUGGUGGCCACCAACGCAGCGCGGCUUCGCUUGAUCGCAGGGCCAGAGAAGCGGCUGCUAGAGAUGGGCCUGAGGCGGGCUCAGGGCCCCGAUGGGGGCCUGACAGCCUCCACCUACAGCUACCUGGGCGGCUUCGACAGCAGCAGCAACGUGCUAGCGGGCCAGCUGCGAGGUGUGCCGGUGGCCGGGACCCUGGCCCACUCCUUCGUCACUUCCUUUUCAGGCAGCGAGGUGCCCCCUGACCCGAUGUUGGCGCCAGCAGCUGGUGAGGGCCCUGGGGUGGACCUGGCGGCCAAAGCCCAGGUGUGGCUGGAGCAGGUGUGUGCCCACCUGGGGCUGGGGGUGCAGGAGCCGCAUCCAGGCGAGCGGGCAGCCUUUGUGGCCUAUGCCUUGGCUUUUCCCCGGGCCUUCCAGGGCCUCCUGGACACCUACAGCGUGUGGAGGAGUGGUCUCCCCAACUUCCUAGCAGUCGCCCUGGCCCUGGGAGAGCUGGGCUACCGGGCAGUGGGCGUGAGGCUGGACAGUGGUGACCUGCUACAGCAGGCUCAGGAGAUCCGCAAGGUCUUCCGAGCUGCUGCAGCCCAGUUCCAGGUGCCCUGGCUGGAGUCAGUCCUCAUCGUAGUCAGCAACAACAUUGACGAGGAGGCGCUGGCCCGACUGGCCCAGGAGGGCAGUGAGGUGAAUGUCAUUGGCAUUGGCACCAGUGUGGUCACCUGCCCCCAACAGCCUUCCCUGGGUGGCGUCUAUAAGCUGGUGGCCGUGGGGGGCCAGCCACGAAUGAAGCUGACCGAGGACCCCGAGAAGCAGACGUUGCCUGGGAGCAAGGCUGCUUUCCGGCUCCUGGGCUCUGACGGGUCUCCACUCAUGGACAUGCUGCAGUUAGCAGAAGAGCCAGUGCCACAGGCUGGGCAGGAGCUGAGGGUGUGGCCUCCAGGGGCCCAGGAGCCCUGCACCGUGAGGCCAGCCCAGGUGGAGCCACUACUGCGGCUCUGCCUCCAGCAGGGACAGCUGUGUGAGCCGCUCCCAUCCCUGGCAGAGUCUAGAGCCUUGGCCCAGCUGUCCCUGAGCCGACUCAGCCCUGAGCACAGGCGGCUGCGGAGCCCUGCACAGUACCAGGUGGUGCUGUCCGAGAGGCUGCAGGCCCUGGUGAACAGUCUGUGUGCGGGGCAGUCCCCCUGAGACUCGGAGCGGGGCUGACUGGAAACAACACGAAUCACUCACUUUUCCCCACA